AGAGCAGCGUGUAGCAGUUCCCUGUGGAGGAUUAACACAGUGGCUGAACACCGGGAAGGAACUGGCACUUGGAGUCCGGACAUCUGAAACUUGAUCUCCAGCACCCUGCCGGUGGCACUACUGAGAGACGAGGUGCCAGGGUGGUUCCUGAAAGUGCCUGAGCCCCAACUUAUCAGCAAGGAGCUCAUCAUGCUGACAGAAGUCAUGGAGGUCUGGCAUGGCUUAGUGAUCGCGGUGGUGUCCCUCUUCCUGCAGGCCUGCUUCCUCACCGCCAUCAACUACCUGCUCAGCAGGCACAUGGCCCACAAGAGUGAACAGAUACUGAAAGCGGCCAGUCUCCAGGUUCCCAGGCCCAGCCCUGGCCACCAUCAUCCACCUGCUGUCAAAGAGAUGAAGGAGACUCAGACAGAGAGAGACAUCCCAAUGUCUGAUUCCCUUUACAGGCAUGACAGCGACACACCCUCAGAUAGCUUGGAUAGCUCCUGCAGUUCGCCUCCUGCCUGCCAGGCCACAGAGGAUGUGGAUUACACACAAGUCGUCUUUUCUGACCCUGGAGAACUAAAAAAUGACUCCCCGCUGGACUAUGAGAACAUAAAGGAAAUCACAGAUUAUGUCAAUGUCAAUCCAGAAAGACACAAGCCCAGUUUCUGGUAUUUUGUCAACCCUGCUCUGUCUGAGCCAGCGGAAUAUGAUCAAGUGGCCAUGUGAAUUCCAAAUAUUUUUAAUGGGGUCCAGUUCUCUAUGGAUUCUUACAUUUAAUUUGUAGGGAAAUGCCAUUUUUCCCCCUUAAACAAGGCAUGGGGCUCACAAGUCUAUGGAGACAGGCCAAAAAGAAUGUGGAGAAGAAAACUGAUAAAUACACAGAGGUCCUCAAGACCCAUGGACUCCUGGUCUGUACCCAAAAAAGCUGUUCGUUCCUCAAAAACAAAAACAAGGCUUGGCUGGGAAAACAGGCCAAUGCCCCGGCAAGAAAGGUUGAGAUCAGAUGUUAGGAAGAACUUUCAGGUAAAGUAUGAGAACUAUGGAGUCCAUCAGCAGAGAUAGUAGUGAAGUCUCUCCCCAGGGAAAAUUUUAAAAAGGUUGAAUCAGCUGUUGUAGAGUUCUAUUUGGCAAUCUCAUGGUUAAAUGACUUCCCUUUGAGCUCUUUAAUUAUUGGCAAUAAACAACUUCUUUAAAAGUUUUAAAUAAAAUAGCAACCACCACCA